UGCCAGCGGCGGAGUCUCCAACUGGGAGAGCUGCAGCUGCCGAGAGGAGGAGAACGCUGAGGUCGGUCGGACCAACGGACGCGCUGACCGCUGCCAACUGCAGCUCGCGCUGCCUCCUGCUCGCGCCGUGCCACUAAGGUCAUUCCCGCCUCCGAGAGCCCAGAGCCGAGAUGGAAACGGUCCAGGAGCUGAUCCCCCUGGCCAAGGAGAUGAUGGCCCAGAAGCGCAAGGGGAAGAUGGUGAAGCUGUACGUGCUGGGCAGCGUGCUGGCCCUCUUCGGCGUGGUGCUCGGCCUGAUGGAGACUGUGUGCAGCCCCUUCACGGCCGCCAGACGUCUGCGGGACCAGGAGGCAGCCGUGGCGGAGCUGCAGGCCGCCCUGGAGCGACAGGCUCUCCAGAAGCAAGCCCUGCAGGAGAAAGGCAAGCAGCAGGACACGGUCCUCGGCGGCCGGGCCCUGUCCAACCGGCAGCACGCCUCCUAGGAACUGUGGGAGACCAGCGGAGUGGGAGGGAGACGCAGUAGACAGAGACAGACCGAGAGAGGAAUGGAGAGACAGAGGGGGCGCGCGCACAGGAGCCUGACUCCGCUGGGAGAGUGCAGGAGCACGUGCUGUUUUUUAUUUGGACUUAACUUCAGAGAAACCGCUGACAUCUAGAACUGACCUACCACAAGCAUCCACCAAAGGAGUUUGGGAUUGAGUUUUGCUGCUGUGCAGCACUGCAUUGUCAUGACAUUUCCAACACUGUGUGAAUUAUCUAAAUGCGUCUACCAUUUUGCACUAGGGAGGAAGGAUAAAUGCUUUUUAUGUUAUUAUUAUUAAUUAUUACAAUGACCACCAUUUUGCAUUUUGAAAUAAAAAAACUUUUUAUACCAUA